AGUCCGGGUUUGGAGACUCCUGCGUCCUCCGACUUUUCAUGGAAGAGAUGUCAGGAGAAAGUGUGGUGAGCUCAGCGGUGCCAGCGGCUGCUACCCGCACCACUUCCUUCAAGGGCACGAGCCCCAGCUCCAAAUACGUGAAGCUGAAUGUGGGUGGAGCCCUCUACUAUACCACCAUGCAGACGCUGACCAAGCAGGACACCAUGCUGAAGGCCAUGUUCAGCGGGCGCAUGGAAGUGCUCACCGACAGUGAAGGCUGGAUCCUCAUUGACCGCUGUGGGAAGCACUUUGGUACGAUACUCAACUACCUUCGAGACGGGGCGGUGCCUUUACCCGAGAGCCGCCGGGAGAUCGAGGAGCUGCUAGCAGAAGCCAAGUACUACCUAGUCCAAGGCCUGGUGGAAGAGUGCCAGGCGGCCCUACAAAACAAAGAUACUUAUGAGCCUUUCUGCAAGGUCCCUGUGAUCACCUCAUCCAAGGAAGAACAAAAACUUAUAGCGACUUCAAAUAAGCCAGCCGUGAAGUUGCUCUACAACAGAAGUAACAACAAAUACUCAUAUACCAGCAAUUCUGACGACAAUAUGUUGAAAAACAUUGAACUGUUUGAUAAGCUGUCUCUGCGCUUUAACGGAAGGGUCCUGUUCAUAAAGGAUGUUAUUGGGGAUGAAAUCUGCUGCUGGUCCUUUUAUGGUCAGGGCCGGAAGAUUGCUGAAGUCUGUUGUACCUCCAUCGUCUAUGCCACUGAGAAGAAACAGACCAAGGAGCAUGAAGAUAGAAAAAGCAACCAGAUUCUCCCAAUCCUGCUGAGACCACAGCUCUUCUCAUCAGAAAAGAAGGUUCCUUCCCUCAGAGUUUUGACUCCUGCAGUCUCUGGUUGCUGCCACAGGAAUGCUCAGGUCUGGGUGCAAGAAAAUAAAGAAAAGGACUGAGCAUGGUGGCUCACACCUGUAAUCCCGCACUUUGGGAGGCCAAAGCAGAAGGAUUGCUUGAGUCCAGGAGUUUAAGACCAGCCUGGGCAACAUAGCAACACCCCUGUCUCUACCAAAAAUUUUUUAAAAAAUAGCUGGGCAUGGUGGUGUGUGCCUGUAGUCUAAACUACUUGGGAGGCUGAGGUGGGAGAAUCAUUUAAGCCCAGUAGUUCAAGACCAGCCUGGGCAACAUAGCAACACACUCAUCUCUACAAAAAGUUAGUUGGGCAUGGUGAUGCAUGCCUAUAGUCUCAACUACUUGGGGAGGCUGAGGUGGGAGAAUCAUUUGAGCCUAGGCGUUCAAGGCUGCAGUGAGCUAUGAUUGUGCCACUGCACUCCAGCCUGGGUGACAGAGCAACACUCCCUCUCAAAACAAAAAAGAGAAAAGAAAGAGGCCCUUGGACUCCCGUCCUGGCUCUGCCCCUAACCAGCUUCACAAACACAAGAACACGCCACUCCUGAACCUGGUCUGUGAAUCAAGAAACAGUUGGGAUCAGACCAUGUGGUCUCUAAAUCCCCUUGCUCCUUAUUAAGCUCUAAAAAUGAGAAGUCUUAAAAUUUUAAAGCUUAAUUAGCCAGAUCCCAUAUCUUUUAAAAAAAAAGGAAAGAAAACCAGGAUUUCCUCCCAGCCUCUCUGCCUGUUAGACUCUGUUGGCCUCCCUGGCCACUAGAGACCUUCUGGAGGUCUUCUGUCCUGGUGCCAUUUCAGGGUUUCAGGCUGCAUCAGUGCUGGCAGCAGCAAACAGUAAACUCACUGUUGGGCAUUACUCCAAAUUCUGUUGUUUCCCCCAUCUGCCUGCCAUGAUUUACUUCUGAGUCCACAGUUAGCUGCUGUGUGCAUCCCAUUCUGGCUUUGUAGUGUCAGUGAGGAAGACGGGGUAGAGUGUGCCUGCUCCAUUUUUCCCAGAACCUCCGAAUUCCACCCUGAAAGUGGAGUCUAGUCUGAUCAAAUGUGUGGGACCUGCUUAUGUGGCCCUCUUCCUGUUCAUCACACCUUAACCCUGAAGGGCAAUGAGCAAACACAAUGAUUUGCCAAACAGCAGAAGGGCUCAUGCCCAUUUCGUGGGAGUCCCCAGCUGGACCCUGUACAAAAAACUGCUUUAGAGACUGCUUUAAGGUGUGGAAGGACUUCUGUGCAAGGUUGCAGCUCUGUUAGGAGAAGCAUAUUAGCACUGACCUAAAUGGCCAUCCAAGUAUGGUUAAUUGCAUUGUCGUAUUUAUAAUUCCUUGAUACAGAAUGAUCUCUAGGUUAAGUUAGGCACAAGAGGAAGACAUGUACAACUCUGUGUGGUGGGCCACCUUGUGUGUUUUUUGAAGUGUGUGAAUAAAUAUGUGUAUUACACAUAUUUACAUGCACAGAAUCUUUGAGAGGGUAAAAUGAUGAGAAACUGUACCUUUAAGAAGGGAAACUAGGGGCAGGGAGACCUGUUUCUCUGCAUCCCCUUGAUUUUCUGUGCAUUUAGCACCACAUGUAAGUGUUGCCAUUGAAAAUAUCAGUUUAUUUAAAAAUAAUACUGGUGGCCUUCAGCAGAAUCCCAGGGGCCUGAUUUAGCCUGGCGGCCCUGCUUAAAGUCCAGGUGUUGGCAGAGGGGGUGGGCCAUAACUUACCUGCCCUGUAUACUGUGGGAACACAGGUGGAGUUUCCCGAAGCCCGGAUUUAUGAGGAGACCCUGAACAUUUUGCUGUAUGAGGCCCAGGAUGGCCGGGGACCUGACAAUGCGCUCCUGGAGGCCACAGGCGGGGCGGCGGGGCGCUCCCACCACCUGGACGAGGACGAGGAGCGGGAGCGGAUCGAGCGCGUGCGGAGGAUCCACAUCAAGCGCCCUGAUGACCGGGCCCACCUCCACCAGUGAGCAGGCAAGAGACCGAGCCGCCCUCCUCUCACCGCCCCCACUCCCUGCCGUGCUACACCCAGAUCCUGUGCAGGCUGCCGGGCCCCUUCUGCUUCCCUUGGAGCCUGGAGAUACUUUUGUAACAAGCCAGAUGAUUAUUUUGGUAUUGCUUGACAAGGCAAAUUGAUUGUCUUGACCCAGGCGUAUGACCCCUGUCGUUGAACAAGCUGUGUCUAAGAUCUCUACUUUUCAUGAGAAUCUGAGACUCUUUGGAGCCAGGCUUUCUCGGUUCUCAGAGGAAAAGUAUGAAUGAGUGUGAAGUGUAUGUGAGAACUUUUGUUUGCAAUAUUUAUUUUUGUGGGUGUCGACUUCCUAUGUGGGCUUUUUGGGUGACACUCCCUUAAGGGUUCAGUUUGACAAUUCUGAGAGUUGUCCUGCAGUUGGAGGCCACCAGAGGUAUCUGAGCUCCCUGCUUCCUAUUUCAUAAUCCUCCAGCCCCAGCAGGUCCACUCCUGGUUCCUGUGUGUUUGGCCCGGGCACAAUCCCCACUGCUUUGCUAGACGUGCUUUCUGCCAUGUGGCUUUGGGCCUAGAGCUUGUUGAUAAUUGCAGCUUGUGGCAGUGGAAAUAUGGCUGAAUGAGCGUCUAAAUCGUUGAGACCAGUGCAACUUUGGGUGCAAGGCUUUGUUUAGGGAUCAAGCCUUUUGCCACCUUGGGCUGGUCUUUGGCCUGGUGCUCACUGGGACCCCAUAUGUCUGCGUAGGAGCAGAACUUUCCAUGGCAGUAAGUGUCCAGCUCUGUUUCUGGUUCUUUCCCCAACUCCAGCCCCGUCCAGUUGUUCUCCUGAUUGACCCGACUCCACUCCAGGAAGGCCAUCUGACCCUGUGACAGGCAUAGCUCAUAAACUACCCCUCCCUGGGAUCCCGCUCCUCUUCAGCCUCCUUCCCCAUGAAGCUGGGCUAACUUUCUAAGUCAUUUUGCUUAGAAAUUCAGUGUGGCCCAUACCCUUUGUCCUCCCAGCCUGGCAUCCAGGCAGGGACACCCUCACACCACCAGCCCCAGGGAGCUUCCCUGCUAUAAACACAGACCCCCUUGUCUUUGCCUCUGAUUUUUACACAGUGUAGAGUGGCCAGCAGUGAACAGGUUGAGGAUGUGCGGGUAGAUAGAUAACUUUGGGUCUGGUUUGUGUCUGUGUUCAUGUUUGUUUAAGGGAUAUGUGUGACUGUGGGUGGGGACGUGUGCUUGUGGGGCACAGGUGGCGGCCCCUGCUGGAGCCCGGCUGGGCGCAGCGCCUAUGUAGGACGGGUGUUCUCAGUGACCUACCUCCCAGGCUCCUCUGCACCUGCAAAGGAACAGGAGUGAGUCGUGACUGACAGGGGUGGUUGAGACUAGACUAGGUAGAGUAGUUACCAGGAGAUGUGAAUGUGCGUCAGGUGAUGGAUGGGUUUGUCAAGGGAAUCGUUACCGUUUUAUACCAAAGGUAUUAACAUGGGCAGCCUUUGACACAUGUAUUCCAAAAACGAGUUUAUAUUUUCAAACGGUUUUUACAGCUUAGACUUUGUACUUACUGCCCUGCCUGUGACAGUUGUAUGCCUUCAUUUUGUAUCCAACAGCAAAGUCUACAAUAAAACUUUAAAACAA